CUCCUCCCCGGACCCGCAGAGGCCUGGCAGCGCCGCGUUUGAGGAGGGUUCGUGUCAGGAAGUCAAGGCUGGAUGAUCGCUUAAGCCCAGGAGUUAAAGACCGGCCCGGACAACAAAGCGAGACCCCGUCUCUCCAGAAAAAGAAAAAAAGAGAGAGAGAGAGAGAAAUUAGCCGGGCGUGGUGGCGUACGCUUGUAGUCCCAUCUACUUAGGAGGCUGAGAGGCCUCUCAAUCCUCCCUCCAUGAUCUUCGCAUAGAGCACAGUACCCCUUCACACGGAGGACGCGAUGGCUCCCAAGAAACGCCCAGAAACCCAGAAGACCUCCGAGAUUGUAUUACGCCCCAGGAACAAGAGGAGCAGGAGUCCCCUGGAGCUGGAGCCCGAGGCCAAGAAGCUCUGUGCGAAGGGCUCCGGUCCUAGCAGAAGAUGUGACUCAGACUGCCUCUGGGUGGGGCUGGCUGGCCCACAGAUCCUGCCACCAUGCCGCAGCAUCGUCAGGACCCUCCACCAGCAUAAGCUGGGCAGAGCUUCCUGGCCAUCUGUCCAGCAGGGGCUCCAGCAGUCCUUUUUGCACACUCUGGAUUCUUACCGGAUAUUACAAAAGGCUGCCCCCUUUGACAGGAGGGCUACAUCCUUGGCGUGGCACCCAACUCACCCCAGCACCGUGGCUGUGGGUUCCAAAGGGGGAGAUAUCAUGCUCUGGAAUUUUGGCAUCAAGGACAAACCCACCUUCAUCAAAGGGAUUGGAGCUGGAGGGAGCAUCACUGGGCUGAAGUUUAACCCUCUCAAUACCAACCAGUUUUACGCCUCCUCAAUGGAGGGAACAACUAGGCUGCAAGACUUUAAAGGCAACAUUCUACGAGUUUUUGCCAGCUCAGACACCAUCAACAUCUGGUUUUGUAGCCUGGAUGUGUCUGCUAGUAGCCGAAUGGUGGUCACAGGAGACAACGUGGGGAACGUGAUCCUGCUGAACAUGGACGGCAAAGAGCUUUGGAAUCUCAGAAUGCACAAAAAGAAAGUGACGCAUGUGGCCCUGAACCCAUGCUGUGAUUGGUUCCUGGCCACAGCCUCCGUAGAUCAAACAGUGAAAAUUUGGGACCUGCGCCAGGUUAGAGGGAAAGCCAGCUUCCUCUACUCGCUGCCGCACAGGCAUCCUGUCAACGCAGCUUGUUUCAGUCCCGAUGGAGCCCGGCUCCUGACCACGGACCAGAAGAGCGAGAUCCGAGUUUACUCUGCUUCCCAGUGGGACUGCCCCCUGGGCCUGAUCCCGCACCCUCACCGUCACUUCCAGCACCUCACACCCAUCAAGGCAGCCUGGCAUCCUCGCUACAACCUCAUUGUUGUGGGCCGAUACCCAGAUCCUAAUUUCAAAAGUUGUACCCCUUAUGAAUUGAGGACGAUCGACGUGUUCGAUGGAAACUCAGGGAAGAUGAUGUGUCAGCUCUAUGACCCAGAAUCUUCUGGCAUCAGUUCGCUUAAUGAAUUCAAUCCCAUGGGGGACACGCUGGCCUCUGCAAUGGGUUACCACAUUCUCAUCUGGAGCCAGGAGGAAGCCAGGACACGGAAGUGAGAGACACUAAAGAAGGUGUGGGCCAGACAAGGCCUUGGAGCCCACACAUGGGAUCAAGUCCUGCAAGCAGAGGUGGCGAUUUGUUAAAGGGCCAAAAGUAUCCAAGGUUAGGGUUGGAGCAGGGGUGCUGGGACCUGGGGCACUGUGGGACUGGGACACUUUUAUGUUAAUGCUCUGGACUUGCCUCCAGAGACUGCUCCAGAGUUGGUGACACAGCUGUCCCAAGGGCCCCUCUGUAUCUAGCCUGGAACCAAGGUUAUCUUGGAACUAAAUGACUUUUCUCCUCUCAGUGGGUGGUAGCAGAGGGAUCAAGCAGUUAUUUGAUUUGUGCUCACUUUUGAUAUGGCCAAUAAAACCAUACCGACUGA